ACUUGUCCUGCUCCUGCUGCUCGAGGACGCUGGAGCCCAGCAAGGUGAGUGGUCCCAGGGGAGUGAGCGGCGGGGGAACCUCCGUCGGGGCUGCGGGUCUCUUGGCCCCUGAACAAAUCUGCAGACGCUGCAGGGAGGCGCGGUGCGCUUUCGUGCGUGGCCGGACCUGGCUGGGUACUCACGGGGUUGAGUUGCAAAGGCAAGGUCUUGCCCGUCUGUCCCCCAAGUUGGCGCGGCUUUACUUUUUGGCAAGGCCAUUUAUUUUUCUGAAAGGGGGACGUGAGACCCUGCUAUGAAAGCCUCGUUGAUAUUAGGUCCUUCUGGGGAAAAUUUUGGGGAGGAAAAAGAACCUUUGGAGGUAAUGACCCCUAAAGUUAAGCUGCACGGAUGGAUGGACACUGUAGGAAGGCAGGUUAAUUAAAUAGCAUCUUAAGCCUAUUAAAGGUAAGUGGUGGUAAUUAUGAUCCUUUGUGAAAGAGCCCGGGUUCUGAAGCGAAUGGAAUAGUUUCUGCUUAUCUCUGAGUCUUGGAUUCAGAACAUGUUCUUUACAAUCCAUCAUUGAGGCUGGUGGUCUAGACUGCCUUGGUCAAACACUGGGUCUGACCCAACGCUAUGCUAAUUUGCCCAAGUGAAGCUCUCCACAUUAAAAAGGUAAGCCUUUCCAGAAAGUGACAAAACUUUUUUUUUUUUCCACCUACAAUCCUUGAAAAACCUGUUCCAGAAACAGGCAAAACUGUUUAUUAAAUACUUAUCAUAAUGGAAGGAGAAUGCAGGGUGAUUUCUUUUCCCCUUUAGUACUGUUUUCCCGUAGUGUACCACACUUUUUGAAUCAGUUUGGCAUCAGUUUUUGAAAAGAUAUUUCCAUUGCAUUUUCCAUUUUAUUGCAGUGGGAAGGAUAAGGAUUGGAUUGUUACUUAUUGCUAGGAAGAGAGUUUUUUAAAAAGAAAAUUGUUCUCUGCCUUUAAGCCCAGCUUUAUGUUGCUCUCAUGGUUUUCAGUGAAGUAUGGAAUCAUGGCCUGUCAUUAAGAAGAUGCCGAACCUUGACAGGCAUGUGGAAAUAUAAUCUCUGUAACUAUAAGGAAAAAAUGUAUUUGGCAAACUGACCCCUUACAUCUAGACACGUUUCUAUAUAGAGUAACUCAAAAUUUAGAUGCUUAGCAUUUAGGUUUUAGUUAGAUCGUCUUCUAAAAUUACUGAACAUCAUCAUCAUUUAAUAUAUUAAAGUGUGAAAUCCUUCUUUCCACUGUAGAGAUGUAUUUCCCUCCUGGUAGGGGGGAAAACAGGCUUAUAUAUGGCUAACACUUAGGGCUUACUUUGUGGCUGGAACAACUGGACUAAGUGGUUUGGGUUUAUUAACUCCUUGAAUCUUCACUACAAUCAGCUGAGAUAGUUAUUGUUAUCCCAGUUCAAACGUAAGGACAUUGAGACACAAAGAAUAUAAGGUACCUUGAUGCAGGAGGGCAUAUUACUCCAUAGGCAGAGUACUCUGCUUUGCUUGUUUCUGGAUCUGAUAGUGUUUGUAUCAUGUUAUUAAAAAAAAUCUUGGAACAGUAUAGAAUCAGUUACAUGUCUACCUUCCAAAUGAGGGAUUGCCUUGUUUUUAGAAAAGGCCAGUCUACCGGGCGCGGUGGCUCACACCUGUAAUCCGAGCACUUUGGGAGGCUGAGGCGGGCAGAUCACGAGGUCAGGAGAUCGAGACCAUCCUGACCAACAUGGUGAAACCCCGUCUCUCCUAAAAUACAAAAAAUUAGCCGGGCAUGGUGGCACAUGCCUGUAGUCCCAGGUACUCAGGAGGCUGAGGCAGGGGAAUCGCUUGAACCCGGGAGGCGGAGGUUGCAGCGAUCGCGCCACUGCACUCCAGCCUGGCGACAGAGCGAGACUGUCUCAAAAAAAAAAAAAAAAAAAGAAAAAGAAAUAGCCAGUCUAAUCAGACAAGCAACAUUACUUCAUUUUUUAAGGUUUAAUAUAAUUUUUUUUUACCAGAACAUUUUAACAAAUACAUUUCUCUUUAACAGUGUCAUCUUAUGUAAACAUCAACAUAAAUAGAAAUGAUUCUGAUAAUUAAAAGACUUUUUUUUUUUUUAGUUCUUCUAAAUUGCUUGGGUAAAUUUUGCUAAAUCAUUUAAUAUUUAAUCUCUUUGUACCUCAGUUUUCUACAUCAUUAAGGUGAGCAUGCAUACCUAUCUCAUAGCUUAAUAUAAAUGAAAUGAUAGUAUGCAGGAAUUUUGCAAAGGGAAAAGCUUAAAAUAGCUAUAAAUGAUUAUUACUAAUCUCGAUCUUACUAAGUUGAUAAAUUAAGAGCUAAUUAGGUAUACAUCAUCUGAAAACUCACAAUUAUUUGAGAUUUGAAUUUUCUCAUUUUUAAAAAUUAAAUUUUUUACUCAAAGGACCCUAAAGCAGCCCGUGGUGGAAUUCCUUUUAAGCCAGUCUUCCCAGUCUAACAGAUGUUCUUUAGGGUCUACUGAUAUUCCCUCACAUAACCUGAAAAGAAGUCUGUUUAAAACACCUUUAGAAUUUUUAAUGGGAUUUGUACAUGUUGUAAUGUUCAGCUACAAGGUAGAGUUUUUACUCUAUAAGAAGUCUUAAGACUGGAAGGAAAUAAACUGUUGACAGUUGUUGUCUUUUGGUGGUAAAAUUGUGGGACAUUUCUUUAUACUUUUCUAAAUUUUCUGUAAUUCGCAUAUAGUCAGAAUAAAAAUUAAACUGCAAAAAAGGUUUCUUUGAUAGAUUUUUUUUCUUUAUUUGACAACUGAAGGUAGAAAUGCAUCUAGUAUGGAGAGGUAGAAAUGUGCUUCAGUGUCUUUUUUCUUUCUGACAUCAUUUUGAAAUAGCAGAAUAUAUUACCUUCAUUCCAAUUAAUGUCAUACAUAGCUAUUCCUCAAUAGAUUUUCUGUUCACAAUGACCUUUCUUUUUAUUUGGCUCCGAAUAAAAUGUAUCAUUAGUUUGAAAACUUACCGACUUUUCACAACAGAUGUAUUUUAACCAGUUCUGUUUCACUUAUAAAUUUAUAAAUAUAUUCUGUUUACCUCUAUUUAUUAUGUUGAUGUUUCACAUAUGGCUUGUAUUUGUGUAGAGUUCUAAGUUGGAUAUCAAGAAGUUGGUCUUCGAAAUCUUUUUUAUUGAAGACUUUUUUUCUGUAAAAUGUACCUCUCAAAAAAAUUAAAUUGGUGAAACUUAUGCUGGUAGCAUAUUUGCUAUUGUAUUAAAUUUAUUGGAAGUUGAUGGUUUACUAUGAUUUUAGGUCUCUGGUUUCCAUUAUGACUGUAGGAAUUUGGGUUACUUCAUAUCAGGAGCUCAGCUUCCUCAUUUGUAUCCUGGAAGGCUUGCCUACUUUCUUGGUUAGAAUGUAAUUUGAACAUGGUAAAAUAUCAGGGAAUUAAUUCUUAAAAACCAUUAAGCCUGAUUUGUUUGGGCCUAUUAAUAUAUAACAUGUUGUGAAGAUAUUAGUUUUUCUUUGCUAAUUUAAUCUGUGAAACAAAUCAGGUUCAUUCUUAAAAAGGAUGUUUCAGUUAUUUGAACAUAUUUGGAACCAAUAUGUGAAAAAGUUUAUAUUCUGUCAAGGAAUGCCUUUAUUUGCUUGUGAUGCAGGGAAAUAUUUUUGAACAAUAUUUGUGAGUUGCCAGAAAAUAAAAACUUAUUUCUCUCUGCAAAUAAACAUUUGUAAUUAUUUUUCACAUUGACAUUAGGUUAAUUUAGAAAUUUCCAUUGUCUUUUCUUUGUCUGAUAAAACAUUGGGGCUCUUAUCCAGUUUUGUUCAGAAGCAAAUAAAUCAAAGCAUCCUUUUCUGCUAUAUUUCUAAUUAAUUUUACAAAAUGAAAAUUAGAAGCAGCACACAAUCCACACGUGUGAAUGAUCAGAUUGAAACAGCACAUUUUUGAAACUUGUAAAUGAAAAAUUGAUUCUAAGAUUGCAGGUAAAUUAUAGGUAGAUUUCUCAGUGUUAGAAACAAAAAGAACAUAUUAUUUUCCCUGGGGAUAGUUGAUAAUUCCAUUUGAACAUCUGAGCCUCAUUUUAAAGACAAACAUGUAAAAAUAUCUUAAAAUGGUGGAAUUGGCAUAAGUAAAAUACCAGUAGUAGAAUUAAAAUGACAAAUUAAUUUCCAAAAGUUAAUAGAUCAUGUAUGUGGGAAAGGGCUAGAUUUACAUAGGAGUAGAAUUUAAAUUUAGGACUACACUUAGCAAAGUGACACUGGGAAGUGAAGCUCAGGUAGUAAUGUUGGACAUUAAUUGAAUGCAUACAAGUAGACAGUUUCUGCUUCCACUUCUUGAUAUAUUUGGAAGGAUAUGGAAUGAUGACCCAACAGUAGAAGGAUGAGGAAAAGCUUCAUAAAGAUAGUGAUAUUUGCUAAGUGUGAUUGUUGAAAUAUGAAGUGAGACAAUUUGGCAAUUUUUCUGAUGUGGCUCCUGGAUUCGGUUUUCUUUAUAACAACCUUACGGCCAUAGGACUUUGUAUUUAUUUUUAAAUAUUGUAUGGAUAACAAUGAUUAUUACUCAAAACUAAAAACGUAGAUGAUUAUCCACAUUUCUGUCUUCUAAUCCAUCGACUUAUAAUUUUUAACUUUCCUUUCUAUUACAUAUUCACAUACCUGCAUAAUCUUUUGUAGUUGUAAUUUUAAUAGUGUGUUCAUGUAAAAUUAACUUAUAGGCUAAUUUAGCACACAUAAGCAUACCUACAAAAUACAGUAAAACAAAAAUUUCAAAAUGCAAAAUUUUAUCAUAAGACAUUCAGUAUUUAUAAAGUAAUUACUGUAUUGUUCAGAGCUGUUAUUGUAUUUAAUUGAAUUCUUCAUUCUGGAGAAAAAUCUUUGAGAAAGUAUUUCAGUUCAAAAUGUUAGUUUAGAAACAAAUAUCAGGCUAAUUUUUCAGUUCAUUAUUUGGGUUAAAUUAGUACAACCUAUGAGGACAGAAAAUACAGAUAUUCAAAUAAACUAGUAUCUAAUGAGUGCCAGUGCAGUACCCACUGAAGCUGAUGAGAUACUCAUGAUUUCCAAGGGCUACUAAAACAUCAUUCACCAGCUGAACGUGCACCCUGAUGGGUGUGUAAUUGAAAGAAAAACUUUGAUUUGCUGCUUGAAUUAUGGGAGAAUCCCAAGAUGCACGUUCCCUCAACUGCUUUUUAAGGAGAGUGGCCCAGAAUUCCCUGCAAGGCUUUUGUUGAGUAGGGUGUGUGCAACCUUGCCUUCAAAACUGAAUUGCCUGGGAUCAAAGAGAAGGUAUUGGCACUCUUUAUCAUUCUCUCAUUAAGAACUAUCAGUAUGAAGGGGUACCAACUGUGAACUCUCAAGAGAGUGUGCAUGUACCUCAGUAUAGUCCUGAGACAUUCAGAGAAGAGUAAAACAUUGUUAUUGUCUUCAGAGAACCUACAGUCUAUUUGAGAAAGUAAUUCAAGUUGGAAUAUAUAUAAUAAUAACCAAGGAAGGAUAUCAGAAGGUUAUGUAAGGCAGAGAGAACUCACCACUCCUGGAGAAGCAGGAGACGCCUACUAUAAUAAUAAUCAAGGAAGGUUAUAAGAAGGUUGUAUAAGGCAGAAAAAGCUCACAACUCCUGGAGAAGUAGGAGACGCCUCACUGAUAAAGUGGUUUUAGAUUGGUAAGCUUUGAAGUUUGGUAGGUUUCUUGUCCACAAGGAACAGCAGAUAUUUGAAGAGUAAGAUCAUAAGAUUAUAACCUGGGGAGUCAGGAAAGUGGGAGUGUGAAAGCCCACCCUUUUAGAAUGAGUAGCAAAACUCAUUCUGGUCAUGCUCCACUGUUUGCUUCUUGAACUCAUGCCCUGUGUCUGCCCAGUUAUUGGAAAAACGUUGGUUGGUUACUGUGGGCCAGGCAUGGUACCACAUGCUGGGGCAUUUUCCUCUUGGAGCUGUGUUAAUGACUUCCAUAGUGUUGCCAGCAGCCCCUUUAUCAUCUGUAAGAUACCGUCCAAACUCCUUUGCGUAUCAUGUAAGUAAUUUUUUUCACAGUCUGGUCCCUCCCUUUCACUCUGACUUAAUCUAAUGCCAGCAUUUCUCACACUGUAUAGUUCAGAUAUGAGACUGAGCUAAUUUUAUUCUUCUAAGAUAUAAUUUCAUGCCAUUUUGCCUUGUUCCCUAUACUAACCUCUUCAUAUAUGCAGUUUCCUCUACUUGAAAUGCUCUUACUUUCCUUGUCUUCUCGGUAAACUCUCGAUCAGCCUUCAAAACCCUUCUUGGGUAUCAUCCCUUUAUGAAGAGUUCUCGAACAGUCCCCACACACUCAUCUCCGGAUAAUACAUUCCACACUGUAUUCUAAGUAUUUAUUCCUGCCAGCGGAGAGAGUUUUAUUCAUUUUCUUAUUUCUAAUACUUAUCAUAGUGUCUGUCAUUCAAAUUAUGUGAAUUAAGAACCCCAUUUCUAGAGUUAAUCUGCUACCCUGAGCACAUUAUUUGGUUCAUCCCUUGGCACCGGCAUGCACUUCAUGCUGUUGUCCUUUGCCUAAUCCCCGUAAAUUAGUGGUCAGUUCAGGAGCCGGGAACAGAGCCAUGUCUUGACCCUUACUACCUGUUUGCUCAGAGCCUAACAGUCUUCCCAGCCUUUCCCAGUCCCACCUCUUCCCAGGAGGAAGACUCCUUUGCUGCACACCCUUGACUAUGAGAGGAAUCCUUCAAGCUGAAAUUCUGAAAAUAGACAUGCCUACUUCUUAGAAAGCUCUGCUCCCCUCAGAUGGGUCAUCCUUAACAACCGUGACAGCCUAAAUCAGUGCCAGCAAUUUGGGCACACUUUCUCCUUUGCAUGCUUUCAGCUUCUGACUUCAAUAGGCAUCUCCAAUAUUAUAAAAGUCCCCCUAGUUUUUGUUCUCGUAGUUGCCUGUCUCCUUUUUCUUGCCAGUGGAUGUUGCUGGGGAGCAUUCAGGUAGCUUCACUAAUCUGGUGUAAUAGAAAAGUAAUGAGAAAUGGAGGCUGGAACGUAUUGUGGAGGACUUCCCAUUGAGGGGCAGACUGAGGAGUUUGUAUCUGCGAUGUUAGGCCUGACAUUAGCCUCAGGUGCUUCCUCUUUCACCUGGUUCAUUUGUCUGUCACUAGGUUUGGUUAUCUCUUCUCAACUCAGGCACCCCAAAUCCAUCAUCUCAACAAUGCUCUUUCCGUGAUCUUGGACAGUUCCCAAACUUGGGCCCAUGUGAUAAUCCCCAUUCUCUGCUUUCUCUGGUUCUGGAUAGCUCAUAGUUACAAGAUUAAGUCAUGUGGUCAUCGUGAUUAGAUCUGCCACAAAUGAGGUCUGGCUAAUCAAGUCCCAAGUGGGGAUUACUGCUUAGCAGACUAUCUCACUUUGUAAAGCUGAUUUGUACAGCCGAACUCCUGCCCUGCUCCUAAUCCUUGCACAGUAUGACUUCCUCCUGACUGAAACCUUGUCCUCUUCCUCUUUAUCAGAGCACUGCUACAUUGGGGAAUGUGAAUUUUGUUUUGGCAUGCUUUACACUUUGAUGGCACUUUUACUUUAUAUCUGGAAACAUGCUCAAAAUGCCACUGGCUUUUACAUAUCUCUUUUUUCAUUGCUUUGUGGUACCUUGUAUCUCUGCUUUUUUCAGUGACGAGCUUUCUAAAUGGUAAUCUACAUUUGUGCUGUAUAUUUUCUUAGUGACUGGCACACAGCAGAUAUUUGUUAAAUUGUUAAUUUAUUUUUUAACCCUUGCAAUAAAAAAGCAAGGGUUUUGUUUCUGCUUUACUGAAACUGUCAUUUACACUGUCAGAUUUUUGUUUGUUUUGGUUUUUGUUUUAGUUUGAAAAACCAAGCAGCUUUGCCUAUCUUUAUUAUUGGUUUCUUUUUUUUUUUUUUCUUACUACAGUGGUCUUUGAAAAUCUGGAGGCUUUGGACUUGGACAUACCUGGAUUUAAAUAAUAGCCUUGUUGAACUUGACAUCCAGUUACUACUCUAAAUAUUUUAAAAUAUGUAACUCAUCUUUCUUUUUAGACUGUAACGAGGGCUGGGAUUGAAUCUGGGUAGCAAGUAAAUUUUUGUUCAAUGAAUGAAUCAAUAUGUCAAAGAAAAUUUUGUUUCAUUUUACUCUGCAGUUAAAAUUUCCAUUUUUAUAUGUUUCCGUUCCACUAAGACUCACUUUUCCAUCCCUCUUCCCUUUAUCCCCAAUUAUUGUUCCACCCCCAGCUCAGUGAGAGGAGUCAGAGCAUGCAAUAGAGGAAUGUGGCAGAAAGGCAUGACUGUCUCCAGCCCACCCAAAUCUUAAUGUGAGUUCUGUGCUCUCCUUUUUGACCUUUGCUCUGCCUCUUCAGCCUUCUGCCUGUUGGUGUGCUUCAGUGUUUUUUGAUCCCCACCAUCUCAGAUCAUUUUAUCUCUUCUUUCCUGAUAUACCUUUGUUUCUGUCUACUCUUGGCAUCCUAAAAGCCAGCUUUAUAGGUCUGGAUGUGAGGUGGACAUUCUUUUGCAUGCAUGGAGGAAGAGUGUUUUAGUUAGGACUUUUGAGGUUAUAGAGAACAGAAAUCCAUAUCUGAUUAAGGUAGAAGGAGAAACUAUUGGGAGGAUUGAGAGGGGAAGGCAGGAAUGCAGCUAGACUUCAGGAACCAAGGACUCAGCUUAGUUCUUCCCUCUUGUUUCAGUCUGGCUUUCUCUUUGUGGAAGGAAUCAUGGCUGCUGGCAAUCCCGAAGGCUUACGGUUUUAACACGGAGAAAUUCUGUAUUUUCCCUAUUGUACAAGGUCCAGGAAAGGGUGAGUUGGCCCUCACAUUGACCCAGUGUGAUUCAGUACCCACCCUUGGACCAGUCAAAUAACCAGGGGGCAUGAGGUCAUAUUAAAACUGUUGGGAAACUGCAGAGCACCUUCCAGAGAAGGAUAAGGCAGGGUACUAGAUAAACAGAGGCAUCCUCUUCUAGGAGAAAGAGUGUUACAUUUAUAAAGAGACCACUGUAUUUUAAAGAAGUUCUUACUGAACCUUUACAUUUAUCUUGGGAGAUGGGUGGUGGUAUCCUCAUCCGUGAGGUAGUUGCAUCCUCACCAGUAUACUGGUUAGGGUAUGUAAGCUUGUGGCAGUUAAGUGUCCAGGAUCUUGAAAACUGGCAUGUCUAGAAUUUGAAUCUAAGUCUGUUGGACUCCAAAGCCUAUGUACUUUCUAAUGUGUUAGUUGUCUACCAUAACAUUAGUUUAGGCUUAUUUCUCAUUCAACAGCAUGUGCUAAGAGCCUUGUAUGUUUUAUUUCUGUGUGUAUGCUUAUAAAGGUGAGUAGAAUGCAUUGCCUUUCUAACCAAAUUUUAUAGGUUGGUAUGGUAACCUGACAUAAAUAUGCAUAAUUAAGCAUAUUAAGUACAGAAAGAUAUUAUUAUGGAAAUAGGGAGAAACACCAGGAGCUUCAGAAAGGUUUCACAAAGAAAAUAACAUUGAGUAGGUAUUUGCUAGGUGGAUAAAAGGAGGAGGGACGUUAUUCUUGGCAGAGUGGAAUGUUAAGUGCAGUGGCACAGAGGUGAGAGCGUGGAGCAUGUGGGGAGUCACCUAUAGUUCAGGACUGUGGAACAAAGAGGUUGUGGGAAAAGUGAAGAGAUGAGACCAGAAAGGGAAUCAGGGGCCAGAUUAUGAUAGCCUUUGUAUCCUGGCUGAAGCAUUUGAACUUCGUUGUAUCAUCAGUGGAAAACAGUUAAAGGAUUUCUAAAUAAGGGACCUACAUGACCCAGUUAGUAUUUAAGAAACUCUGGCUGAAGUGUGGACAGUGGAUUAGAGGGAGAAAAGAUAGAAAGUGGGGAAACCUAUUAGAGAACUUUGCAAGGGCCUGCACUUGUUCAGAGGGACUAAAUUUAGAACUGCUAAGGAGAUAAAAAGUAUAAAAUAUAAUGAUUAGUUAAAUUUGAGAGAGCCAAGUCAGUUUAAUAUUGAGAUUUUUCUUUCUGGAAUCUUCUUCCUCUUCCUGCAUUCCACUUCUCUCAUUCACCAGGAUUUCUACCUAGCUAACUGCUUGCUUGCUUGCUUGCUUUUUUCUUUCUUUCUCUCUCUCUCUCUCUCCCUCCCUCUCCCUCUCUCCUUCUCCCUCUCCCUCUGUCACACAUGCACACACACACACACAUUCUCACACUCACACUGAAGCACUCAUUACUUCCCUGUAGUACUCAUCAUCCCUGGAAUGACUCUCUGUGUUUGUCUUACUCCCUAUAUUGUAAACUCUGUAAGGACAGGGGUCUUGUCUGACAUUUUUACUGUUGUUCCUAAUACCUAGUAGCACACUGCUGGACAUGUGGAGGUUGUUCAUUGAAUGCGUAGGACAUGUGGAGUUUCAAAUGAAGUGGAACUUCUGAGCAAAAGUGCUUAGUAUGUAUAUAGAUAAGAUUGAAGACUUUGGAGCUUUCUCCAUUUAGUGACAACUGAAGUCAAGGAGUAGAUUGCCCACAUAGAAUACAGAGUGGGGAAAGAACUCUGAAGAAUAGCAACAUCAACAGCUGGUAGUAACAAGGUUACAUACAGUUAAGGUCUGCGAGAUGCAGUUGGAGGGUUAAAGGAAUUAAGACAUGGGAGGAGAGAUUUAAGAAGGAGGGAGGGGAGAUAUGAAGUAAGGGAGAAGGAAGCAAGAGAAGGAAGUGCCAGCAAUGCCAGAUGCUGUAGAAGGUAACAAAAGAUAAGGAUGGAAAAUUCUCCAUUGGCUUUUGGCAGCUCAGAAACUGACUGCUUUAGUGAAGAGUUUCAUUGGAUAUGUAGAUCUGUGUGUUUCCUAGGGCAGCUGUAACAAAGUACCACAAGCUUAACUGACUUAAAUUUAUUGUCUCACAGUUAUGGAGGCUAGAAUUCUGACAGCAGGGUGUGCAGAGGGCCAUGCUCUUUCCUAAGACUCUAAGGUGAUGGAUGUGGACACACUGUACUAGGCCCUGAGAGUGGAACCCUUACAUCCAUAAACUACCCACAGACCUAUCCCAACAGCACUGUUUGUGAAUGGGAGAUCCGUGUAAAGAUGGGAGAGAGAGUUCGCAUCAAAUUUGGUGACUUUGACAUUGAAGAUUCUGAUUCUUGUCACUUUAAUUACUUGAGAAUUUAUAAUGGAAUUGGAGUCAGCAGAACUGAAAUAGGCAAAUACUGUGGUCUGGGGUUGCAAAUGAACCAUUCAAUUGAAUCAAAAGGCAAUGAAAUCACAUUGCUGUUCAUGAGUGGAAUCCAUGUUUCUGGACGCGGAUUUUUGGCCUCAUACUCUGUUAUAGAUAAACAAGAUCUAAUUACUUGUUUGGACACUGCAUCCAAUUUUUUGGAACCUGAGUUCAGUAAGUACUGCCCAGCUGGUUGUCUGCUUCCUUUUGCUGAGAUAUCUGGAACAAUUCCUCAUGGAUAUAGAGAUUCCUCGCCAUUGUGCAUGGCUGGUGUGCAUGCAGGAGUAGUGUCAAACACGUUGGGCGGCCAAAUCAGUGUUGUAAUUAGUAAAGGUAUCCCCUAUUAUGAAAGUUCUUUGGCUAACAACGUCACAUCUGUGGUGGGACACUUAUCUACAAGUCUUUUUACAUUUAAGACAAGUGGAUGUUAUGGAACACUGGGGAUGGAGUCUGGUGUGAUCGCGGAUCCUCAAAUAACAGCAUCAUCUGUGCUGGAGUGGACUGACCACACAGGGCAAGAGAACAGUUGGAAACCCAAAAAAGCCAGGCUGAAAAAACCUGGACCGCCUUGGGCUGCUUUUGCCACUGAUGAAUACCAGUGGUUACAAAUAGAUUUGAAUAAGGAAAAGAAAAUAACAGGCAUUAUAACCACUGGAUCCACCAUGGUGGAGCACAAUUACUAUGUGUCUGCCUACAGAAUCCUGUACAGUGAUGAUGGGCAGAAAUGGACUGUGUACAGAGAGCCUGGUGUGGAGCAAGAUAAGAUAUUUCAAGGAAACAAAGAUUAUCACCAGGAUGUGCGUAAUAACUUUUUGCCACCAAUUAUUGCACGUUUUAUUAGAGUGAAUCCUACCCAAUGGCAGCAGAAAAUUGCCAUGAAAAUGGAGCUGCUCGGAUGUCAGUUUAUUCCUAAAGGUCGUCCUCCAAAACUUACUCAACCUCCACCUCCUCGGAACAGCAAUGACCUCAAAAACACUACAGCCCCUCCAAAAAUAGCCAAAGGUCGUGCCCCAAAAUUUACGCAACCACUACAACCUCGCAGUAGCAAUGAAUUUCCUGCACAGACAGAACAAACAACUGCCAGUCCUGAUAUCAGAAAUACUACCGUAACUCCAAAUGUAACCAAAGAUGUAGCGCUGGCUGCAGUUCUUGUCCCUGUGCUGGUCAUGGUCCUCACUACUCUCAUUCUCAUAUUAGUGUGUGCUUGGCACUGGAGAAACAGAAAGAAAAAAACUGAAGGCACCUAUGACUUACCUUACUGGGACCGGGCAGGUUGGUGGAAAGGAAUGAAGCAGUUUCUUCCUGCAAAAGCAGUGGACCAUGAGGAAACCCCAGUUCGCUAUAGCAGCAGCGAAGUUAAUCACCUGAGUCCAAGAGAAGUCACCACAGUGCUGCAGGCUGACUCUGCAGAGUAUGCUCAGCCACUGGUAGGAGGAAUUGUUGGUACACUUCAUCAAAGAUCUACCUUUAAACCAGAAGAAGGAAAAGAAGCAGGCUAUGCAGACCUAGAUCCUUACAACUCACCAGGGCAGGAAGUUUAUCAUGCCUAUGCUGAACCACUCCCAAUUACGGGGCCUGAGUAUGCAACCCCAAUCAUCAUGGACAUGUCAGGGCACCCCACAACUUCAGUUGGUCAGCCCUCCACAUCCACUUUCAAGGCUACGGGGAACCAACCUCCCCCACUAGUGGGAACUUACAAUACACUUCUCUCCAGGACUGACAGCUGCUCCUCAGCCCAGGCCCAGUAUGAUACCCCGAAAGCUGGGAAGCCAGGUCUACCUGCCCCAGACGAAUUGGUGUACCAGGUGCCACAGAGCACACAAGAAGUAUCAGGAGCAGGAAGGGAUGGGGAAUGUGAUGUUUUUAAAGAAAUCCUUUGAAGAUGAUGCUGCUUUUUACAAAGCAUCGUUUUAAAGCACAUGGCCUUUUUUUUUUAAUUAUUAGUGGUAGUAAUAUAUAGAAUGUAUUACAUAACUGUCACUGAAGUGGUUGGGGAAAAUGUGGUGACUGAGGUACAGGAAACUACUAAUCUUGCCAUCUUGCUUUAAGGUGUUAUGGUGGCACAGUUACUGCUCGCCUGUUAAAUUUCAAAUGUCCUGUUUGAUACUACUGUAGAACACUAUUUUUAAUACAGAAAAAGCUCCCUAUAAUGCACUUCAGAGAAAUUAAAAAUCACAGAGUAUUUAUUACCAAUGCUGCAGGUACAUUAAUGAACUCGAGAUGGCUCUGUAAGCCUGACUGGCAAUAACGCACGGUACUGUUCUUGAAAUACCUAAUGGCUUGAAAUUCUAGUCUGUUUGUGAAAGAUGGGUACUAUCAUGAUUUCCUCUUCUAUUCCUAUAUUCUUUUCUGGAUUUUUUUUAAUAAUUAGUGAUAUAAGCAUUGUUUUUAUUGCAGCCAUAUCCACUUAUCCAUCUUAAGAUCUGUAGCUGGGAUUUUCUGACUUGUAAUGAGCAGGGGGAUUGCUUUUUCACUUUGUGACACUCUUUAGAGCUUUAAUGCUUCACAGUAUAUGGCCUGGUCUCAUCCUUGCGUGUUCCACUUGAGGCCCUUUGGUGUCUUGCCCCAUUCUUGUGUUUAUAAAAUGUUUGAGUAUUUCUGAUGAGUGAUGCUUGCCUUAGUCUCAUGAAUUCAGAUCCCUUCAUGUCCUUUAAGUAUGCUCCUCAAUGUGUAAACAGGAACAACUUUAUGAUUUGAAAGCUUUAAAGGAGAUUCUUCUCCCACCCCCAACUUUAUUUGCAAUGGGAUUUUUCCUAGGAGAGUUAUGAAAAGUUGAAGGCUUCUAAGGGAAUACUGUAAACAUGACCCACUUAUAUUUAUCACAGUGAAAGGCAAAAUUAUUCACUCAGAAGUAAUAUAAAUUACCUCUUUAAAAAGUAACCAGAAUUUGUCCUUUUUGGUUUUAUACAUUCACAAACAUAUACAUUUUUCUUGAGUCUCAAGGUAUUUUAUAUUUUUAGUCAGAAAAAAUAAUUUUUCAUUUCAGUUUUCCAUAAACUGUUACACAAAAUAUAAACCUAACGUGUAUUUUUCAGGACUGCGUGAUCGUGCACUUUGUGUGGUAAGAGGUUUGAGUAGUCCUAUAUGUCACCUAGGGAACAGACAUUAUAGCUUACUAGCAAAUGAAUAUUCAUGCCUUGUUUUUGAUACCUCCUGGCAGCUUCCAUGUCACCACUUGUUCAUACCUGCCCAGAGCUAGUUUUAGACAUGGCAAAAUAGAAAUCAUCUGUAAUUUAUUAGCUAACAAUGUAAAACCAUCUUUUAAAGCCUUCAGACUGUCAAGACGACAUGAGCAGCUCACCAUAUGAUAAAAAUACAUAAAUUUGACAUUCCCUCUUCCAUAAACCUUUGUUUGUAGAUUUAAUGUUGAACAGUACUUUUCCAUAAAGUUCUAGUCACUUCUGUUGGCCUGAGCCACCAGAUUAUGAUGUUGCCAGAAUUCACUCAAUUUGAAUAAAGAUGAACAGUAUUUGUUUUCUUGUUUCCAUGAAUUAUAUCAGUAUUCUAAAACAUCGCUUCAGAAAGAGAACUGUUUAUUUCUGCAGGCUUCCUGUCCUUUUGUGGUAUGGUUUUUUGGCCUUAUUUUCACUGGCUUUUCCUUCUCCAAACUUUGAGGCGUGAUUUCAUUCAUUGAAGAAUCAAUACAUAUUUUGUUUCAAAAUGUUUGAAACAAAAGACAUAGAUGGUAGACUUUUAUUAAAACAUAUAUGGAUGUGGAAAGCACAUAUAUUAAUGCAGUCAUCCCUUUUCAGGUGGGAAGAGAGCAAACCAGUUGAUUUUUUAAUUCAUCCUUAGUACACAGAGAAUAUACUUUUCCUCAAGUAAUAUACCUGUUUGAAGCUUUAAGAGAGAUGUUUUUGGUAACUAUUUCAUUUUCCCAAAGAAGUUUGCUAUUCUUGUGUUAAUUGUGUAUACCUGAUUGUUUUUUCCUGGAGGUUUUUGUUGUUGUUGUUUAGUUUUGGGUUUUUUUUUUUUUAAGAGGGGCAAGUGUUUUCUGAAAUGAUGCAUAUUUUAAGACUCGAUUCAUAUUGCCACUGUGCUAUCCUUGAACUACCAAUAAUUUUUAUAAAAUAUCUAGUUUUUACUACUUUUAUAUAAACUUUACUUUCCAGAUGAAGAGCUGAGCCUGAUUCAAAUGGUUUUUCUGCUUUAUACUUCUUUUUAGUUCAUUGGUUUUUAUAGUAGAGGUUUUCUAUUUUUUUUUUUUUUUUUUUUACUACAUUUAUAUGUCUGAUACAUAUACGGCUUUGGAGACAAUCAAGUAACAACUGAAAAUGUGAAAGUAACCAUAUCUGACAAAAUUCCCUUGAAUUUUUAUCCUUUGCUUGCAACAUUUAAGACUCAAAGUCACUGGUAUAUUGGAUUAAGUUUUUUCCUGUUAAUGCAAUUAUAGAAAUACAUCGGAGACACAACAAAUGUGGCCAUUACAGGUUUCAUAAAAUUACACUGACUUGGCUGUUACUUGAUCUUAGGAAACAGCACAGUUUAAGAUAUUGUGAAUUCUGACUUAUACUUUAUUAAAUGCUGUAAAUCUAAAUAGAUCCUGUUGGAUGUGAUGGGUCUAGUCCAGUUUAUUUAAGUUCAUGUUUCACUGUUUGCACUUUGCAUUGAACAAUGGGUUUAUUCGCUGAUGUAAACGGUUCGAGUGAAGAAUUAAUGCAGUAAGUAUGACAACACAUACACACUUGCCUCUCCCCAUCUCCAGAAGAGGGGAGCAGAGUCCGAGCUUAUCUAAAUAUGAAUGUGGCCACAAAGCUGUGGAAGGUGACAAAGCUUAAACACCUUUGCCCUGGCUCUGCAUUGUCACCUAGAGAGCAAGAGGUCUAUAGAAACAUCAUGUCACAUGAAACGAUUCUCUGCUUUUUGGUUCUGAACUUGAAGUCCCUAAACUGCAAAAUCUAAGAGUUGGGUGGUUAUUAAAAUGCUUUUAAAGUCAACUGUGGCACCAAUUCUAAUGUAAUCCAACUUGUGACUGUUUUUUUUUGUUUUGUUUUGUUUUUGUGUGUGUGUGUGUGGCACUGGGAAAAGUGGAAACAAACAUGUAUUGAAAUACAUAUUGGAAAUAAAAAUGGUUUGAGCGUCAGUGAUAUUCUCCCAGAAUGUACUUAUCUUACCUCGGCAUGUACUGUAGUCACUCAGUAUUUGUAUAUGUUGCUAGAAUUUAGAUUGUAAAAUAGUGAAAUUUUAAUGUGUUCAUUUGUUUUUAAUGUAUAUAUGUCUUGCUCAGAUUAUUUGGUUUAAAUAAAACAACCUUGAGGUUUGUAGCUUUUCCUUAUACUAUAAAAUGCCAGAUUCUUCUAUUUUAACCUCA